AGUCGGGCCGCGGCGCGUCGCUGCGCCGCACGUGUGCGAGCCCGGCCGCCGGUGAGUCGGCUGGAGCGCAUCUGGUCCUCCGCGCGGAAAGCGCUGCUUUUGCCUGGCCGCCCUAGCCGCUGGCUCAUCCAAGUGGCCUUCGCCGCUCUCUUGCGUCCCAACCAGAGCGCUGGCCACCUCGCCGCCCAGCUCACGCCGCGCCCGCGCUCCCAGGCUCCGGGUUUUCUUAAAUGUUUUCUUGGAGCCUUAAAGAUGGAGAUGACAGAAAUGACUGGUGUGUCGCUGAAACGUGGGGCACUGGUUGUCGAAGAUAAUGACAGUGGAGUCCCAGUUGAAGAGACAAAAAAACAGAAGCUGUCGGAAUGCAGUCUAACCAAAGGUCAAGAUGGGCUACAGAAUGACUUUCUGUCCAUCAGUGAAGACGUGCCUCGGCCUCCUGACACUGUCAGUACUGGGAAAGGUGGAAAGAAUUCUGAGGCUCAGUUGGAAGAUGAGGAAGAAGAGGAGGAAGAUGGACUUUCAGAGGAGUGCGAGGAGGAGGAAUCAGAGAGUUUUGCAGACAUGAUGAAGCAUGGACUCACUGAGGCUGACGUAGGCAUCACCAAGUUUGUGAGUUCUCAUCAAGGGUUCUCGGGAAUCUUAAAAGAAAGAUACUCCGACUUCGUUGUUCAUGAAAUAGGAAAAGAUGGACGGAUCAGCCAUUUGAAUGACUUGUCCAUUCCAGUGGAUGAGGAGGACCCUUCAGAAGACAUAUUUACAGUUUUGACAGCUGAAGAAAAGCAGCGAUUGGAAGAGCUCCAGCUGUUCAAAAAUAAGGAAACCAGUGUUGCCAUUGAGGUUAUCGAGGACACCAAAGAGAAAAGAACCAUCAUCCAUCAGGCUAUCAAAUCUCUGUUUCCAGGAUUAGAGACAAAAACAGAGGAUAGGGAGGGGAAGAAAUACAUUGUAGCCUACCACGCAGCUGGGAAAAAGGCUUUGGCAAAGGUCAGAACUGCAGCAGAUCCAAGAAAACAUUCUUGGCCAAAAUCUAGGGGAAGUUACUGCCACUUCGUACUAUAUAAGGAAAACAAAGACACCAUGGAUGCUAUUAAUGUACUCUCCAAAUACUUAAGAGUCAAGCCAAAUAUAUUCUCCUACAUGGGAACCAAAGAUAAAAGGGCUAUAACAGUUCAAGAAAUUGCUGUUCUCAAAAUAACUGCACAAAGACUUGCCCACCUGAAUAAGUGCUUGAUGAACUUUAAGCUAGGGAAUUUCAGCUAUCAAAAAAACCCACUGAAAUUGGGAGAGCUUCAAGGAAACCACUUCACUGUUGUUCUCAGAAAUAUAACAGGAACUGAUGACCAAGUACAGCAAGCUAUGAACUCUCUCAAGGAGAUUGGAUUUAUUAACUACUAUGGAAUGCAAAGAUUUGGAACCACAGCUGUCCCUACGUAUCAGGUUGGAAGAGCUAUACUACAAAAUUCCUGGACAGAAGUCAUGGAUUUAAUAUUGAAACCCCGCUCUGGAGCUGAAAAGGGCUACUUGGUUAAAUGCAGAGAAGAAUGGGCAAAGACCAAAGACCCAACUGCUGCCCUCAGAAAACUACCUGUCAAAAGGUGUGUGGAAGGGCAGCUGCUUCGAGGACUUUCAAAAUAUGGAAUGAAGAAUAUAGUCUCUGCAUUUGGCAUAAUACCCAGAAAUAAUCGCUUAAUGUAUAUUCAUAGCUACCAAAGCUAUGUGUGGAAUAACAUGGUAAGCAAGAGGAUAGAAGACUAUGGACUAAAACCUGUUCCAGGGGACCUCGUUCUCAAAGGAGCCACAGCCACCUAUAUUGAGGAAGAUGAUGUUAAUAAUUACUCUAUCCAUGAUGUGGUAAUGCCCUUGCCUGGUUUCGAUGUUAUCUACCCAAAGCAUAAAAUUCAAGAAGCCUACAGGGAAAUGCUCACAGCUGACAAUCUUGAUAUUGACAACAUGAGACACAAAAUUCGAGAUUAUUCCUUGUCAGGGGCCUACCGAAAGAUCAUUAUUCGUCCUCAGAAUGUUAGCUGGGAAGUCGUUGCAUAUGAUGAUCCCAAAAUUCCACUUUUCAACACAGAUGUGGACAACCUAGAAGGGAAGACACCACCAGUUUUUGCUUCUGAAGGCAAAUACAGGGCUCUGAAAAUGGAUUUUUCUCUACCCCCUUCUACUUACGCCACCAUGGCCAUUCGAGAAGUGCUAAAAAUGGAUACCAGUAUCAAGAACCAGACGCAGCUGAAUACAACCUGGCUUCGCUGAGCAGUACCUUGUCCACAGAUUAGAAAACGUACACAAGUGUUUGCUUCCUGGCUCCCUGUGCAUUUUUGUCUUAGUUCAGACUCAUAUAUGGAUUUCAAAUCUUUGUAAUAAAAAUUAUUUGUAUUUUUAAGUUUUUAUUAGCUUAAAGAAAUAAUUUGCAAUAUUUGUACAUGUACACAAAUCCUGAGGUUCUUAAUUUUAGCUCAGAAUAUAAAUUAGUCAAAAUACACUUCAGGUGCUUAAAUCAGAGUAAAAUGUCAGCUUUACAAUAAUAAAAAAAGGACUUUGGUUUAAAGUAGCAGGUUUAGGUUUUGCUACAUUCUCAAAAGACAGCAGGAGUAUUUGACACAUCUGUGAUGGAGUAUACAACAAUGCAUUUUAAGAGCAAAUGCAACAAAACAAAUCUGGACUAUGGAUAAAUAAUUUGAGAGCUGCCACCCACAAAUAUAAAUACAGUACUCAUGCUGACUGAAAUAAUAAGACAUCUACAAAUUUAUAAACAAAAAGUGAUUGUCAUUAUCCUGCUUAUGUACUAGAUUCAGGCAAGCAUUAUAGACUUUUUGGUUGCGGUGGCUUUUGCAUUUAUAUUAUCAAUGCCUUGCAGGAACGUUGCAUUGAUAGGCCCAUUUUAUUUUUUUAUUUUUUUUUUCGAGACAGGAUCUCACUCUGUAGCACAGGCUGGAUUGCAGUGCAAUCCUGCAAUUCUCAAUCUUGCACUGCAGCCUCGACCUCCCAGGCUCCAGUGACUCUCCCACCUCAGCCUCCUAAGUAGCUGGGAGUACAGGCGCGCACCACCACGCCUAGCUGAUUUUUGUAUUUUUUUGUAGAGACGGGGGUUUGGCCAUGUUGCCGAGGCUAACUCCUGGGAUUACAGGCAUGAGCUGUGCUGGCCGGGUUUUUUUUUCUUGAUGUAAACGUGUACAGCUGUUUUAUUAGUUAAGGUCUAAUUUUUACUCUAGGUGCCUUUUAUGUUCAGAACUCUUUCCACUGGACUGGUAUUUGCUCAAAAAUAAAUAAUGGUAGAGAAGAAAACUAUAAAAAUGGACAAGGCUUUCUUCUAUCAGUAGCGUUUACCCUUUGUCACCAGUGGCUUUGGUAUUUCCAUGUCUGGCAUUGCAUAAACUUCUCUGGUGUGAAAGGAUAAAUAUGCCUUUCUAAAGUUGUAUAUCAAAAUUGUAUCAAUUUUUAUUUUCUAUGAUUUCUAGAAACAAAUGUAAUAAAUAUUUUUAAAAUCUCCUUUCUACUGGUUAUGUAAAUAAAUCAAAUAAAUAUAUCAAAAUGAGUGCAGA